AGUCGCAGCCAGGAGCGGCCGCAGACGGAGCGCACCUCGCAGCUGCCGGGCGGGCCCUGGGGGGAGCUGCGUCCAGCAGAGCUGCUGGGUGGUUGCUCCUCCCGGGCUCUCAUCUCCGGUAUCCGGGCCGACCCCCGCACCCCCUACUUCCCUUGCCCUCGCUGCUCUCUCCUUAGAGGCGACUCUUUGGGGAAGGGCCAGCAAUCCCGCCUUCCCCGGCCCCAGUAGUCACCCACUCUCCCACCCCACCUCUGUUCCUUUUCGCGGCCCCGUCUCCCGCGCCCUCAGGCGCCCAGAACGCCCCGGCCAUGGGCAUCCGAGGCAUGCUGCGAGCCGCAGUGAUCCUGCUGCUCAUCAGGACCUGGCUCGCGGAGGGCAACUACCCCAGUCCCAUCCCGAAAUUCCACUUCGAGUUCUCCUCUGCUGUGCCCGAAGUCGUCCUGAACCUCUUCAACUGCAAAAAUUGUGCAAAUGAAGCUGUGGUUCAAAAGAUUUUGGACAGGGUGCUGUCAAGAUACGAUGUCCGCCUGAGACCGAAUUUUGGAGGUGCCCCUGUGCCUGUGAGAAUAUCUAUUUAUGUCACGAGCAUUGAACAGAUCUCAGAAAUGAAUAUGGACUACACGAUCACGAUGUUUUUUCAUCAGACUUGGAAAGAUUCACGCUUAGCAUACUAUGAGACCACCCUGAACUUGACCCUGGACUAUCGGAUGCAUGAGAAGUUGUGGGUCCCUGACUGCUACUUUCUGAACAGCAAGGAUGCUUUCGUGCAUGAUGUGACUGUGGAGAAUCGCGUGUUUCAGCUUCACCCAGAUGGAACGGUGCGGUACGGCAUCCGACUCACCACUACAGCAGCUUGUUCCCUGGAUCUGCAUAAAUUCCCUAUGGACAAGCAGGCCUGCAACCUGGUGGUAGAGAGCUAUGGUUACACGGUUGAAGACAUCAUAUUAUUCUGGGAUGACAAUGGGAACGCCAUCCACAUGACUGAGGAGCUGCAUAUCCCUCAGUUCACUUUCCUGGGAAGGACGAUUACUAGCAAGGAGGUGUAUUUCUACACAGGUUCCUACAUACGCCUGAUACUGAAGUUCCAGGUUCAGAGGGAAGUUAACAGCUACCUUGUGCAAGUCUACUGGCCUACUGUCCUCACCACUAUUACCUCUUGGAUAUCGUUUUGGAUGAACUAUGAUUCCUCUGCAGCCAGGGUGACAAUUGGCUUAACUUCAAUGCUCAUCCUGACCACCAUCGACUCACAUCUGCGGGAUAAGCUCCCCAACAUUUCCUGUAUCAAGGCCAUUGAUAUCUAUAUCCUCGUGUGCUUGUUCUUUGUGUUCCUGUCCUUGCUGGAGUAUGUCUACAUCAACUAUCUUUUCUACAGUCGAGGACCUCGGCGCCAGCCUAGGCGACACAGGAGACCCCGAAGAGUCAUUGCCCGCUACCGCUACCAGCAAGUGGUGGUAGGAAACGUGCAGGUUGGUAUGGGCCAGGCCUCGAGAAAUCCCACCCUGAUACACUCUCCAUGGAGAAGUAUGUAAAUCCUUUCGUGAAGAAAGUGAAACCUCCACCUUCCUCUCCAAUAAAUAAAAGUGGCUGCCCCAUCACACCACCAGACAAUGGCUAACUACUUGGAAAUACCCAAUUUAGUAUUAGAUAAUGAGUCAGGAAAGGUUAGGUGCUGCUAUUGUGACAAUCCCAAAAUCCCAGUGACUUGACCCCCCAAAAAUGUUUAUUUCCUUCUCACAUUGCACAUCUAAUGCAGGUCAUCAGGGGAGCUUCUGCUCAUGGUGGCAACUCAGGAACAAGCUGACAGAGAUUUCAUCGUGUGCUUCUACAAUCUUUGUAGUAAGGGGAAGGGAAAGUAGUGGGGCUCACACUAGUAACUAAAUACUGCAGCCAGAAAGGACAUACCUCACUCAAACUCAUGACUCAUUAGGUAGAACCAACACCAUAGCCUAACCCGACUAUAAGGAACCAGGACAUUCAGUUUGCUGUGUACCCAAGAGGGGUGAUCUAUAUAUUCUGGAAUUGCACUAGUGGCAACCAUAGGUGUCUUCCGUUGAUCUUUGAAAGGAUGUUACUUUCUCAUUUCCCCGCUUAAAGGUACUCAUGCCCUCCCUUUGUGGUAGUCUUCUCAUCUUAAGCCAGUAACAUAUGCAAAAGUUCUAAAAUACUGCCAUUCAUCAGUAAGAGUGUCUACUGUAGGUAGUAUUCAGGAGAAGCUCCAGGCAGAUAGUCAUUCUCCUCAUCCUUUCCCCCCAGGGAAAGGAAAAACAGCCCCUUUGCUAUUUCUGACAGGCUGCACUACCAAAAUCCCAGAGGUCAUGGGAGUCAGGAGCUGAAACCUGGUCCCCAACUGUCUACAGUUUUAGGAGCAGACUUUUCUUGUGUAAGCUUUCUACCUUCACCUCUGAGGUUUGCAAGCAAUAGGAUAGAUAUAUAUACAUAUACAUAUACAUAUACAUAUACAUAUACAUAUACAUAUACAUAUACAUAUACAUACAUAUACAUACAUAUAUACCUAUGAUAGGUAUGAGAGGGAUGAGAAGAGAUUAUUAGGAAAAUUGGCUCACUCAAUUAUGGAGGCUGAGAAGUCCCACAAAAUACCAUCUGCAAACUGGAGAGCCAAAGAAGCCAGAAGUGUGGCUCAGUCUAAGUCCAGUGAAGGCCUCAGAACCACAGAAGCCAAUAGGUGUAACUCUCAGUCCCAGGCUGAAGUCCCAAGAACCCGGAAAGAUGAUGGUGCGAGUCCUAAAGUCCAAAGGCCAGAGAGCCUGGAAUUGAUGUCCAAAAGCAGAAGAAGAUGGAUGUCACAGCUCCAGAAGACAGAUAGUGCAAAUUUGCCUUUCUUCUACCUUCUUGUUCAAUCUGGGUCUCAGCCAAUUGAAUGGUGUCACCCACAUUGAGUGAGGGCAGAUCUUCCUUAUUCAGGCCAUUGAUUCAAAUGCCAGUCACUCCCAGAAACACCCUCAUAGACACACUCAGAAAUAAUACUUUAUCAGCUAUCUGGACAUUAGCCCAGUCAACUUGACACCUAAAAUUAAGUAUCACAGGCUGUAUACCCCAUUCUGGCUAUAAGAAAGGCUAACUGCACCAGAGACACUAAAGCCAAAGCUGAGGAAGAAAAACUCCUCAACAGCUGAGUUGGUCCUGGGCACAGUGAAUCUGGAGAUGACCCAAACCUUCAGUGAACUCUCUCACGAAAACACAAGUCAACCUCUUUUGGAAUCUCAGGGUUCCUGAGUUCUGAUGAGGGCCCUGUCAAGAGUGAGGGCAGCUAAGAGGAAGUAUGUGAAGCAGAGGUGGGGCAGGUGUUGAUCCGGGUGGGCAUUGAUCAUGGGUGGAUGAGAUUAACACGAAAGCACCCUUCAUCCUACAUGAUCCCCCCAGCAAUCACCCUGGGGCUCAUUUUGAAUGACCCCAUUCUCAUACAGAGGCUGAUUAUCAGCCUGAAGUGUUUCCUACCAGAAGCUGCAAAUCCCAGUUUGAUGGUUGAAGGUCUUCAUUAACGCACUGAAAGGCACCGUUAAGAAAAUGAAAAGGCAAGCACAGACUGGGAGAAAAUAUUUGCAAAACACAUGUCUGAUACAGGACUUGUAUCCAAAAUAUACAAAGUACUCAUAAUUCAACAAUAAGAAAACAAAAAAAAAUUAAAAAUGGGCAAAAGAUAUGAAAAGGUACUUAUCAAAGAAAACAUACAGAUGGCAAAUAAGCAUAAGAAAAGAUAAGCAUCAUUUAUAAUUAGGGAAUUACAUAUUUAAACAACAAUGAGAUAUCACCACAUCAUAUUAGGAUGCCUAAAAUACAAACCACUGACAAUACCAAUUGCUGGUUAGGAUGCUGAGCAACAGAAAUUCCCAUUAAUUGCUGGUAGUAAUGCAAAAUAGUACACUUGUUUGGAGGACACUUCAGCAGUUUCUUACAAAGCUAAACAUAGCCUUACCAUAUGAUGCAACAAUCAUAGAUUUUGAUAUUUUAUCUUAUUUAGUAGAAAACUUAUCUCCACACAAAACUCCAUACAAAUGUUAUGGCAGCUUUAUCCAUAAUUUCCCAAAGCUGGAAGCAACCAAGAUGCCCCUCAAUAGGUGAAUGGAUAAACAAACUCUGGUACAUUCAAACCUCAGAAUAAAAAUACCAUUCAGCAAUAAAAAUGAGCUAUGAAGCCAUGAAAAAAACACAGAGGUAUUUUAAAUGCAUAUUGCUAAGUGAAAGAAGCCAGUUUGAAAAGGCCACGCACCAUAUGAUUCCAACUAUGUGACAUGCUAGAGAAAGUAAAAUUAUUGAUAUAAAAAGAUCAGUGCUUGCUAGGGAUUCAGGGAGAAAGAGUGAGCAUAAAUAGGUGAAGCACAAGAAAUUCAUUAGGACAAUGAAACUAUUCCAUAUGGUACUGGAAUGGUGGGUAAAUGACAUUGGACAUUUUUUAAAAACCAUGAAAAUAUACAACACAAAGUAAGCCUUAAUGUAAACAAUAGACUUUAGUUAAUAAUAAUUUAUCAACAUUGGUUCAUUAAUUGUAACAAAUAUACCACACUAAUGCAAAAAGCUCAUAAUAAGGAAAAUUGUAUAAGAGGAUGAGGCUACUGGGAACUAUCAGUACUGUCCAAUUUCCUAUAAAUUAGAACUGUUUUAUAAUGUCUAUUAAUUUAAAAUAUAAAACAUACAACUAACACACAACCCAGAUUUCAUACUUGGGCAUUUAUCCUGGAAAAAUGAAAAUGUAUGAUCACACUGAAAGCUGUACAUGAAUGUCCACAGUAGCUUUAUUUAUAAUACCCAAAUGCUGAAAACAGCCCAAAUGACCUUCAAUGGGGUAAUGUCUAAACAAACUAUGGUAGAUCUGUACAUAGGAUACUACUUAGCAAUGAAAAGGAAGAAACUGUUGAUAUAUGCAACAGCUCAAGGGAAUUAUGUUGUUUUCAUUCAGGCUGCUGUAACAAAAUACCUUAAAGUGGGUAAUUUAUAAAUAUUAGAAAUUUAUUUCUCAUAGUUCUGGAGGCUGGCAAGUCCAAAAUCAAGGUGCCAGCACAGUGUCUGGUGGGGGCUCUCUGCUUUAUAAACAGCACUUCUUGCAGUGUCCUCACAUGGUGAAAGGGGCUAACAGCUCCCUCGAACCUCCUGAACUAAUUCCAUUUAUGUGGGAUCCACCCUCAUGACUUAAUCACCGUCUAAAAGGUCCCACCUCUUAAUAUUAUCACAUUGUCAAUUAAGUUUCAACACAUGAAUUUUGUGAGGAUACAUUCAGAUCGUAGUGUAUGCUAAGUGAAAAAAGCUAAAACUCACAAUGAGAGACUACCAUCCACCUAUUAGAUUAGCUAAUAUGGAAAAGACUGACAAUACCAAGUAUUGGUGAGAAUUUGGCAGUUUCUUAAAAUGUUAAACAUGCACCUAUCAUGUCAUGCAAGUAUACCACUUCUAGGUAAUUAUAUAAAACUUCCCCAAAUGUAAAAGAAUCUAUUGUAACAGAAGGCAGAUCCAUGGUUUCUUGGGAAUGGAAGUUCAGGGAGGGGGCUCCUACAGGAGGAAUUAUGAAGGGUAGAAGAAAACUUUUGAGGGUGAUGCAUCUGUUCACUCUCUUUAUUGUGAUGAUGGUUUUUCAGAGGUAUACAUGUGUCAAAGCUUAUGAAAUUUACACAUAAUGCAGGUUUUUUUAUGUCAAAUAUCUUUUAAUAAAGCUUUUUUUCUUAUUCUUCAACUUUUAUUUUAGAUUCUGGGCGUGCAUGUGCAGGUUUGAUAACUGGUUAUAUUGCCUGAUGCUGAGGUUUGGGGUACAAAUGAUCCCGUCAUCCAGGUGCUGAGCACAGAACCCAACAGUUUUUCAACCCUUGCUCCCCUCCCUCCCCAGUCCAGUAAUCCCCAGUGUGUAUUUGGUUUUUGGUUCCUGUGUUAAUUCACUUAGGACAAUGGCCUCCACCUGCGACCAGGUUGCUGCAAAUUGCAUCACAUGAUUUUGUUCUUUCUUAUGAAUGCAUAGUAUUCCAUGGUGUAUAUGUAUGUUUUCUUUAUCCAGUCCACAAUUGAUGGGCAGCUAGGGUGAUUCCAUGUCUUUGCUAUUGUGAAUAGUGCUGCAACGAACAUGCUAGUGCCUGUGCCUUUUUGGUACAAUAAUUGGUUUUCUUUUGGAUAUAUGCCAAGUAAUGGGAUUGCUGGAACAAAUGGUAGUCCUGUUUUGAGUUAUUUGAGAAACCGCUAAAGUACCUUCCACAGUGGCUGAACUAAUUUACAUUCCCACCAAUAGUGUAUAAGCAUUCCCUUUUUUCUGCAGCCUCGCCAACAUCUGUUGUUUUUGACUUUUCAAGAAUAGCCAUUCUUACUGGGGUGAGAUGGUAUCUCAUUGUGGUUUUGAUUUGCAUUUCUCUUAUGAUUAGUGAUGCUGAACAUUUUUUCACGAUGGUUGGCUGCUUGUAUGCAAUCUUUUGAGAAGUGUCUCUUUGUGUCUUUUGCUCAGUUUUUAAAUGGGGUUGUGGGUUAUUUUUCCUUGUUGAACUGUUUAAGUUCCUUAUAGAUUCUGGAUAUUAGACCUUUGUCAGAUGCAUACUUUUGCAAAUUUUUCCCCAUUCUGUCUUGAUACUUACCUUGCUGUGCAGAAUUUUUUUAGUUUAAUUAGAUCUGACUUAUCAAUUUUUAUUUUUGCUGCAAUUGCUUUUGAGGACUUUGUCAUAAAUUAUUUCCCAGGACCCAUGUCCAGAAUAGUGUUUUCUGAUAUUUUCUUCUAGGAUUCUGAUAUGAUUUGGGUCUGUAUUCCCACCCAAAUCUCAUGUCGAAUGUAAUCCUCGGUGUUGGGAGAGGGGCCUGGUAGGAGGGAAUUGUAUUAUGGGGGCGGAUUUCUCCCUUGAUGUGCUCGUAAUAAUGAGUGAGAUCUCACAAGAUCUGAUUGUUUAUAAAAGUGUGUAGCACUUCCCCCCUCUCUUUCUCUUCCUCCUGCUUCAGCCAUGUAAGACGUGCCUCCUUCCUCUUUGCCUUCUGCCAUGAUUGUAAGUUUCCUGAGGCCUCCCUAGCCAUGCUUCCUGUACAGCCUGCCAAACUGUGAGUCAGUUGAAGCUCUUUUCCUUUUCAAUUACUCAGUCUCAGGUAGAUCUUUAUAGCAACACGAGAACAGACUAAUAUGGAUCUUUACAGUUUGAGGUCUUACAUUUAAAUCUUUAUCUUGAGUUAAUUUCAGCAUGUGGUGGUGAAAGGGGUCCAGUUUCAUUCUUUUGCAUAUGGUUAGCCAGCUAUCCCAGCACCAUUUAUUAAAUAGGGAGUACUUUCCUCAUUGCUUAUUUUUGUUGACUUUGUCAAGGAUUAGAUGGCAGUAGGUGUAUGGCUUUAUUUCUGGGUUCUCUAUUAUGUUCCAUUGGUCUAUGUGUCUGUUUUUCUACCAGUACCAUGCUGUUUCAGUUACUGUAGCUUUAUACUAUAGUUUGAAGUCAGGUAAUGUGAUGCCUCCAUCUUUGUUCCUUUUGCUUAUGAUGACUUUGGCAAUUCAGGCUAUUUUUUGCUUCUAUGUGAAUUUUAGAAUAGUUUUUUCCAAUUCUGUGAAAAAAUAACAUUGGUAGUUUGAUAAGAAUAGCAUUGAAUCUGUAGAUUGUUUCAGGCAAUAUAGUCAUUUUAACAAUAUUGAUUCUUCCAAUCUAUGAGCAUGAAAUAUUUUUCCAUUUAUUUGUGUCAUCUGUGAUUUCUUUUAGCAGGGUUUUGUAGUUCUCCUUGUAGAGAUCUUUCACUUCCUUGGUUAGAUAUAUUCCUAGCUAUUCCACCUUUCUGUGGCUAUUGUAAAUGUGGUUGCAUUCUUGAUUUGGCUCUCAGCUUGAACGUUAAUGAUGUAUAGAAAUGCUACUGAUUUUUGUAUAUUGAUUUUGUAUCCUGAAAGUUUGCUGAAGUUGUUUGUCAGUUCCAGAAGCCUUUUUGUGGAGGCUUUAGGAUUUUCUAGGUAGAGAAGCCUAUUGUUUACAAGAGCUGUUUUUCAAAAAUUAUAUUUUCUACAAGAACAAAACAACUUUUGAAAAGAAUAAAAAUAAAAGACUUGGGAAGGGAGAGUAUUUAAUGACUGGGAUUAUUUUAAAAUCCUGGGAUAUGGUGUUAAUUUAAAAAUCAAGACUUUUUAAAUGGGCUUAUUACUAUUUAAAAAUACUCUGUAUGGAUUCAACUGUCUUCAGGAAGAUGGAGUAGAGGUACUUUUCUCUGUUUAACAUGGUAGACAUAACUAAACUGCCUGGACCUUGGCUAUACUACAAGCACAAGAAGAGUCUGAAUAGUGGAAAGAAGAAAGAAAACUCUCUAGUGACCUUGGGACCAAAGGAGUGGCAUGGUGGGGCAUUGCCUGGGUUUCCUUUUGCCUCAUAUAUCCCAGACUUGGAGACAAAGAAGCAACAAACCCAGAAAUGCCAAUGGGCACAGACAAGAAAAGCCCCAACAAAAACUUGCUCUCUCCAGCCAAAGGACCAGGACAGGGGUAACCCAUUAAGGCAGAAAAUGUUUAGACAUUAACUGCUCUACUCCAGCCAGACAACACAGAAAAAAAUGUGGCUCCACCCCAAACAGACAGCAAAGACCAAGUAGUGAGCCCAGAUAUCUAACCUUAUCAGGCUAUACCAAAGUAUUUGAAACCCCACUCGACUGCACCCCACCAGAGAUGGUAACAGAGAAGACUCAGUAGGGGCCUGGGAGUUUGAUUCCUUACCAGUUGGUAAGGAGGCCUAGCAGAGACUCAGGAUUUCAAUAUGGCAUAGAUACUGCAACCACGCCCAACCACCAUGAUGUCAGUGCUCCACAUGGGGAGCAGUAAUGAGGCAGUCCUGCCCCUCCAGGAAGGAGAUAUUCAGGGGAAGUCUAGUAGGGAGUUGGAAUUGCCACCAUUUCCCAACAGUAACAAAGACAACCUCCCUGGGUGUCAGUGGAGGCCAAGCUAGGAACCCAUCUGGCAGUGAUGAAGCAGUGGCCUCCUUCCCCUGCUAGAGCAGUGUCAGAGGAAGUUAGUUAAAAUAGAAGGUUUGAACAAGAUCCAGUCUUAUGGCACAAUACUAAAAUGCCCAGGAUGCAAUUAAAAUAAAAUAAAACCUCAUCAUGCCAAGAAUCAGGAAAAUCUCAACUUAAAUGAGAAUAGACAAUCAAGACAGGCUAACACCAAAAGGACACAGAUGUUGGACUUAUUUUCCGAAAAGUAUUAGAAAUAAAUCAUCAUAAAAAUGUUUCAACGAGUAAUUACAAACACACUUAAAACACAGGAAAACAGAAAGUCUCAGCAAGAAACAGGAGAUAUUAAAAGAACAAAUGGAAACUUUAGAACUGAAAAAUACAAUAACUGAAAUUAAAACCUUAACUGAUGUAUUCAACAGCAGAAUGGAGAGGACAGAAGGGAAAUCAGUGAACUGAAGACAGAGUAAUAAAAAUGAUCCAGUCUGAACAACAGAGUUAAAAAUAGAAGGAAAACAUAAACAAAGCUGCAGGGACCAAUAGGAUUGUGCCAAAAGAUCUGUUAUUUCUACCAUCGAAGUCCCAGAAGGAGAGGAGAAAGAGACUAAGGCUGCAAAUGUAUUAAAAUGACACCUUUUAUAAGGGGAUAACAAUUCAAAUGACAGAGGAUUUAUUUGUAGAAAACACAGAGGCUAGAAAAAGUGGUACAAGAUCUUUCAAGUGCAGAAAACGAUCUAAACAUACCAAUUGAAAUACAGAGAAUAGAAUAGUGGAUUCAAAAAAUUACCCAAUUAUAUGGUGUCUGUAAGAAACUCGCUCAAAUAUAAUGAUAUAAGUAGGUUGAAAAUAAACAUGAAUGUUGAUAACACCUUUAUUUGUAGUAGUCAAAAAAUUGAAACAACUAAAAUAUCCUUCAAUAAAUGAAUGGUUAAACAACCUGUGAUACAUAACUACUCCACAAUAAA